AGCGGCGGCAACAUUGUUUGGUGUUUAUUUUGUUUUACGAUCGAUAGCUUUCUUCGCUGGUUCGGGGCGGCUGCUGAACGGCGGAGUGGCGUGGACCUCAUGUAGCAAUGACAAUGGAAGGGGCCAGCGGGUCGAGUUUUGGAAUAGACACGAUUUUGUCCAGUGCCAGUUCAGGCAGCCCAGGCAUGAUGAAUGGAGAUUUCCGCCCGCUCGGUGAGGCCAGGACCGCGGAUUUUAGGAGUCAGGCCACCCCAUCUCCCUGUUCGGAGAUUGAUACCGUAGGGACGGCGCCUUCUUCUCCUAUCUCAGUCACCAUGGAGCCCCCGGAGCCGCAUCUGGUAGCAGACGCGACCCAGCAUCAUCACCACCUCCACCACAGCCAGCAGCCGCCGCCGCCGGCCGCGGCCCCGACGCAAAGUUUGCAGCCUUUGCCCCAACAGCAGCAGCCGCUGCCGCCACAGCAGCCGCCGCCGCCGCCCCCCCAGCAGCUGGGCUCGGCCGCCUCGGCCCCCAGGACUUCCACGUCUUCUUUUUUAAUUAAGGACAUCUUGGGCGACAGCAAACCUCUGGCGGCAUGUGCACCCUACAGCACCAGCGUAUCCUCUCCCCACCACACCCCGAAGCAGGAGAGCAACGCAGUGCACGAGAGCUUCAGGCCAAAGCUCGAGCAGGAGGACAGCAAGACCAAACUCGACAAGCGGGAGGAUUCCCAGAGCGACAUCAAAUGCCACGGGACAAAGGAGGAAGGAGACCGGGAGAUUACGAGUAGCCGUGAGAGUCCCCCUGUGAGAGCCAAGAAGCCUCGAAAAGCAAGGACAGCUUUUUCCGACCACCAGCUCAAUCAACUGGAGCGUAGCUUUGAGCGGCAGAAGUACCUGAGCGUGCAGGAUCGCAUGGACCUGGCUGCAGCGCUCAACCUCACUGACACCCAAGUCAAGACCUGGUACCAGAACCGCAGGUGCUACUUUUCCUCUGAAACCCGAGCCGCUGGAAUUCCCCCCACUUCAUCCCCAAAUCAAUGAAGCCACACCUUCUCAAAUUGAGACAUCUGUGCAGCUGACACUUAGGUCCAGAGAGCCUGCGCGGUGCACCCCUUGGGCCCACCCCAGGCUGGUUCCAAAGGUUUGUAGCCAACAACACGGCCCGGCCCAGCUAUUGCUAUUCCCACAGAGCUGUCCCACCAGCCUCGGCGUAAAUGUCCUUGCUUUGGCCUGUGAGGCGGCUGGGAGAAGCAGGAUCCAAGCCUUGGUCAGUGUAGCUGCAGAGACUAGGAGAGCCCAGCUGGGUUAGAGUAGGUUUGGCAGCCGCAGCCUGGAGAAUCGGCGGCUGGCCAAGCAUCCGGACAGGGAGAAGGAAGGAGUGUGGGUCUGUCCCCUGUACUGGCUGCCUCUGCUGUCUCAACAUGGAGCUAGAGUGCUGCAGAGCCUGCCUGGCACUGCUCCUUCUCUAGAAGGGAAAUUAAGAAAGCAAAAGUGACUGCCAGUGCUCGCAGGGCCACGAAGUGUAGAGUGGAACCUGGGCAAUCUGAGGCAGAGGUUUUGCUGUGUUUUCAAGCCUGGCACUCAUCUCCUUGUCUCGAUUUUCUCUACCCCUCCUUUUCUCCCGUUUGUGUUCUAAUCGUCCAUAAGUGCGGUUGGAAAUGCCCAUCCACUUGUCAUCUUUACCAUAAUUUUCUGUCUCAUUACAUACGGUUUCAGCCACCCUAAUUCUGUCGGAAAACAUUAGUGUCAUUUGUAGCCAAUUUAAAAUGGGCGACAUGUUUAUUAAUUUGGCUGGAGCUGCCGGGUAUGGAUGGCCCACCAGCCCUGCGUUCCUUCAUAAGGUAUUUGAGCAAACGCCCGCUCUCUUCUUCCUAGCAGGGUGUGCAGCGGGGGAGGGAGGAGACUGAGAAAAGCUGAUCACAGGUUUUAAUUGUUACUUUAUCUCUGAGGAGGAAAUACCUUGAAAUGCAUUCACCCCCACCUCAGAAUGGCCAGGAGGUACUUUGCCCUUGGGAGAACCCUCCCUCAAAUGAAUUCCAUUUUGAGACCUUGUUGCCAUCCUCCCCUUAAGCCCCCUGCCCACUGUAAGGUCCUGUCAGGCUUAUGAGAGAAAUAUGUCUCCCAGCCCUGGGGACUGAGAGGGGCUGGGGUCCCUGGCUUAGGAGUCUCUGCAUCCCUUUGUUUACGGUUUCUUCUCUCACAGCCUGGCGGGGAAGGAAGAGGGGCUGAGAGCAGACUCUUUGGGAUUGUUGGGAGUUGGGAGAUGUGGAAGGGGAACUAAGGAAGGAGGAAAGUGACUGCUUGUGGAAGUCUCCUUUGGCCCUAAGGAAAGUUUCCAGAAGUAGCCAAACUACAAGGGGGGCGACAGCAGAGCAGAGGUUUAGGAAAAGGAAGCAAGGCCUGUAGGAUUUCAUUUGUGAGGGUCUCAGCCACUGAAGGUGUAAUUUACAAAACUGGCUUUGGGUUUGGGUCUUUCUGGGAGCAAGGCUGGGGCAGGAGAUGUGGUGCAUUGCCAGUUUGAAGAGGUCUCUGAGUCUUCCUGCCACCCAGGGAGAAUGAAGGAGGAGGCAGGAAGGGGCCAGAGAAGGGGCCGGGUC